GAAUUUCUCUUGAAGUAACUCAAGAUUUUCCUUUAUUUCCAUGGUUGAGGGCCUGCAGGCCCUAAAAGGGGUCCCUGCUCCGUCUCAGCUGGGCCUAGGUGAAGGUCUCUUCCUUUUUCUGAGACGGUGUCUCCGUCUGUUGCCCAGACUGGAGUGCAGUGGCAUGCUCUCGGGUCACUGCAACCUUCGCCUCCUGCUUCAGCCUCCCUAGUAGCUGGGAUUACAGGCGCCAGCCACCACGCCCAGCGAUUUUUCUGUAUUUUAGUAGAGAGGGAGUUUCACCAUGUUGGUCAGGAUGGUCUCGAACUCCUGACCUCAGGUGGUCCGCCCGCCUCCGCCUCCCAAAGUGUUGGGAUUACAGGCGUGAGCCACCGCACCCGGCCUAAGGUCUCUUCCUUAAAGACUGCCGUUGGACUGAAAGGUGUCCAACCUAGAACAGUUUCGCACCUAGCCCUAUCCCUGUUGGAUGCUCAUUAUUUUUUAAAAUCCAAUUUACCAAGCGUGUUCAGUCUUCAGCUCGCUAAUUUCUCUAACGGCCGUACGUAGUCAAACUGAGAAAACUGUUCAGUGGGGGCGACAAAAGCCAACGCCCGUGAGACAACCCCCAAAUCCGUGGGUCGAUCUCACUUGUUUAAUACCCCAAGCCCUGUCCGGGGGGAAGAAAGACAACCUCCCGAGUCCCUCAAGGCAGGUGCUUAUUUGAGCUUCAGAUCUAAAGCUGCGAAUGGACAGAACCCGCCCAGUGCAGGGUGGACCCGCGAGAGACAGCGCCGCGACAAGCGUUAGAGAGAACGUCCGCCUUGAAAAAAAUGUCACCAGGCAAACUUCCAGUUUCACUCCGACCAGUGGCCCAAGGCCUUUUAUCCUAGUUGGCAGUGGUCCACACCCAAAGGCUACCCCACCCAGCCGCUCCCUCAGGGUUUCUCCACACCCUGUAGAGCCUUUCGCACGUCUCGAGGGUGUGACGGUUACGCCGUGACGUCACUCCAGAGGAAGUGGUAAGACGAGCGCGGUAACGGAGCUCUUGAAGGGCUGCAGCCCUAACACGGAGAAGCGCGCUAAGAGCCUGGAGGCGGGACCAAUUUAUGACUGACGUCUACCCACACCCAUUGCUUUUCUGAUUCCUUCUCAAACAAACCAAUGAAUGCGACGACGGAGACAGCAGCGUGCCCCAGGCGCUAGAAGUGGCUCUGCCCCUUCUACUUUGCUGCCCUUUGGUCGCCAUGCUUAGUGUGGCUACUGCCUCUGUGCUACUUGAGGCUCUCCUACGGCUUUUCGAUGCCUUCGAUGAACCUCUACCUAAGCACUUCUUCCCUUUCACCGCGAACUCCUACCUUCUCGGGUUUCUAGCUUGCUCACUUUACAUCCAGCCACACUGGAGAUGGCGGCCGGAGGCGGGCCCGAGGUGGGGCGUGACCAGCGCAGUGACGUCAGCGCGCUGCGUGUCGGCAGGGAGUGGAGCAACUGCUGUAGUCCAAGCAGCUUAUUGUGCCCCUAAAAAGGAGAAAGUGGCAAUCAAACGGAUAAACCUUGAGAAAUGUCAAACUAGCAUGGAUGAACUCCUGAAAGAAAUUCAAGCCAUGAGUCAAUGCCAUCAUCCUAAUAUUGUAUCUUACUACACAUCUUUUGUGGUAAAAGAUGAGCUGUGGCUUGUCAUGAAGCUGCUAAGUGGAGGUUCUGUUCUGGAUAUUAUUAAGCACAUUGUGGCAAAAGGGGAACACAAAAGUGGAGUCCUAGAUGAAUCUACCAUUGCUACGAUACUCCGAGAAGUACUGGAAGGGCUGGAAUAUCUGCAUAAAAAUGGACAGAUCCACAGAGAUGUGAAAGCUGGAAACAUUCUUCUUGGAGAAGAUGGCUCAGUACAGAUUGCAGACUUUGGGGUUAGUGCUUUUUUAGCAACUGGUGGUGAUAUUACCCGAAAUAAAGUGAGAAAGACCUUUGUUGGCACCCCUUGUUGGAUGGCACCUGAAGUUAUGGAACAGGUCCGUGGUUAUGAUUUCAAAGCUGAUAUUUGGAGUUUUGGAAUUACAGCAAUUGAAUUGGCUACAGGGGCGGCUCCUUAUCAUAAAUAUCCACCAAUGAAGGUUUUAAUGCUGACACUGCAGAACGAUCCUCCUUCUUUGGAAACUGGUGUUCAAGAUAAAGAAAUGCUGAAAAAAUAUGGAAAAUCAUUUAGAAAAAUGAUUUCAUUGUGCCUUCAAAAAGAUCCAGAAAAAAGACCAACAGCAGCAGAACUAUUAAGGCACAAAUUUUUCCAGAAAGCAAAGAAUAAAGAAUUUCUUCAAGAAAAAACAUUGCAGAGAGCACCAACCAUUUCUGAAAGAGCAAAAAAGGUUCGGAGAGUACCAGGUUCCAGUGGGCGUCUUCAUAAGACAGAGGAUGGAGGCUGGGAGUGGAGUGAUGAUGAAUUUGAUGAAGAAAGUGAGGAAGGGAAAGCAGCAAUUUCACAACUCAGGUCUCCCCGAGUGAAAGAAUCAAUAUCAAAUUCUGAGCUCUUUCCAACAACUGAUCCUGUGGGUACUUUGCUCCAAGUUCCAGAACAGAUCUCUGCUCAUCUACCUCAGCCAGCUGGGCAGAUUGCUACACAGCCAACUCAAGUCUCUCUCCCACCCACCGCAGAGCCAGCAAAAACAGCUCAGGCUUUGUCUUCAGGAUCAGGUUCACAAGAAACCAAGAUCCCAAUCAGUCUAGUACUAAGAUUAAGGAAUUCCAAAAAAGAACUAAAUGAUAUUCGAUUUGAAUUUACUCCUGGGAGAGAUACAGCAGAGGGUGUCUCUCAGGAACUCAUUUCUGCUGGCCUGGUCGACGGAAGGGAUUUAGUAAUAGUGGCAGCUAAUUUGCAGAAAAUUGUGGAAGAACCUCAGUCAAAUCGAUCUGUCACUUUCAAACUGGCAUCUGGUGUCGAAGGCUCAGAUAUUCCUGAUGAUGGUAAACUGAUAGGAUUUGCCCAGCUCAGCAUCAGCUAAACCACAACCCUGGAAGAGGCGGCCUAAGGAGAUUCCACACAUGCGUAUCUCUGUUGCUUCUAUUGGCCUAAACCCACUACUGCCAAAGAACCCAGCAACAAACCUCCCGGCUAGGAGCUUUAGAAGUCUUUAUGUUCUUCCUGCCAUCAUUCCUCCUUUUCCCACAGGGAAAGAAAAGUUGGAUCACUAGUGGCCAGCAUCCCCAGAGUUCCGUUAGUAAACUUACUUCAUAUGUCCCCUGUCUUCCUCCAUCUGAGAAGUGGCCCAUGUGCUUCAAGGCCCAGGAGGGAGAUCUGUCAGCUCAUUCUUGCCUUACUCCAAUGAUGGCCCAGGUGGAAAAGUAGCAGCUGUAUCGGGCUUCCUCAUCCUGCCUGUUCCCCCACACCUGCCAGGAUAUGGACAUCUUGGGAUAUCUCUUUACCACUGAAGUAGAAUUGAUUGUUCAGCUGGAGCCCAGAGAAUUUAAUUUAAUGUUUUUUCUUUGUACCUGAUGUGAAUUCUAGCAACCUUUGUUAGGAAAAAGCACAGCCUCAGAUGGAGGCAGCCUAAACUGUGUUCUUGUUUUGUUCAUGGUGUUUCUAAGCGUUUUGCUGAAGCUGCUCUCAGGCACCCCCUUCUUCAUUGCUCUCUCCAGAAAGGGUUGCUAGCCUUAACUUCAGCUGGUGCAAAACAUCUGACUGUAGCCGAACUUCAGCCAUCAGAUCCUUCAAAGUGGAACUUUGGAUUGUUUUUACAGACAACAUCGAGUAAUGGCUUGUAAAUGUGAAUUUUGCCAGAGGUGGUUUUUGAACAGGAAAAUCAUAAUUCAUAUCAUUGGAGAAGUAUUUAUUUUCAAAUAUCAAAUUGAAGAAAAACUCAAUCCUCCCAUGAAAAUCAGUUCGCCUGGCCUCCAAGUCGUGAGGAAAUGGGUAUGCAAGGCUGAGAUUUCUACAGCAAUAAAGGAGACACACACUGGGCCAGAGAGGCCUGCCUUCUGCCUGCUCUCCUGCACUGACCCUUUGGAGGGGGUCUCUGUGUGCUGAAGCUAACUCAAGAUGGAAAGUGAAACCACAUGUGCCGUGACCUUUAGGUUUUAUGAGUAGACAGUGUUCAUUUGAUUUUCUACAGAAAUAAUAUAAAUUAUUCUUUAGGUUUAAAAAAGAGCACUCAUAAUGCAAUAUGUGAAUAAUCAGUGAGGUUGAUUUUUCUUUUUUCCUACCGUUUCAUAGUCUUUGUCUAACUGCUAGUAACCCUACCGAGUUUUAUAUAUGAGUGGGAUACUCAAUCUGGCCUUAAAAAGAUACACAAAGAUGGGCUGUGGGUCCCUGGAAAGGGGGAGAGUUGCCCUUUACAGAAUCACUCGAGCCCUUUCCAGCACUGUUGGUCUGAUGAACAAGGUUGUUUUACCUUAUUUUCUCUUGGAACAUAUCUGAAAACCUUCCCCACAAAUAACUUGUCACACCUUUUGUUUCAUUCUGAGUCUUUAGUUUUAGUCAUGGGCUUUCUUCACCUGCUCUAGGUGCAAAGGCAUGUUGGGAAAGAGAUGGAUGUUGGGGAGGAAGAGAGGAGAUGGAUUUCAGUUGGGAGUUAGGAGGAGAGUAGGUGAGAUGAUCAGACACCGGAGUUCAACGUCCCAGCAGUCUUGGUAAAAGGAGGGAGCCUGCUGAGCCAGGAGGGAGAAAAGAAGAUUGACCAGCUUGCUAGAAAAAUACUUAGCUUUUCUUUUUCUUUUUUUGUGGAGGGGGGACGGAGAGGAACAAGGAUGGGGAGGUAGGAAUGAGGUAUAGAAAAGAGAUAGCAUCUUCUUUGGCACAAGACUAGUGGCUUACCGCUUACCUUAGAGUUUUGUUUUUUUUUUUUCAAACCCAUCAAAAUCUACUUAUUUAUGAAUCCAAGGGGUGGCAGCAUCACUCUGUUCUAGCAUUCUUUGUGGAGAUGGUCUGGUGCCUAGCUGGGAGUGAGCAGCAGCCCAUCCCCUGUUCACUUUCUCUAGCCCAUCAUUACCUGUGAACUGCAGUGGGGCAGUCAUGGCAAAUAGAAUUGGGCUGGGGUUUCUCCUUCUUUUCAGUUCAUUGUUUGCCCUGCUAGGAAUUAGAAGACAGACACCAUGUCCCAGGACAGUGUUACUUCUUCUGCAUGAUGUGUGGUAGACUCCCUUUGCUGGCUUGUGCAGUGAUACUGAGAAAAUACAUGAACAGAAACUGCCCAGGUGGAACAGCACGUAACCUAGUGAGUGACUGUACUCCUUUCUAGGAAUGCUGAUUCAGAGUGCACCUCUUUGACUAGGUCCCAGGAUCCCCUUGUCCCUGGAGUAGGGACUAACUAUAGCACAAAGUAAUAUGUGCCAAUGCUAUUUGUGAAAUGUUUGGUCUUUCUAAACGACUAAAGGAUUUGUUGGGUUUUUGCUUAAGUUUUGAACCAAAUCCUAGAGCCAGCUGAUAAUAUUUAAUAAUCUGGAGGAGAGAAUAAUGAUGUACCAAUAAGUGGAGAUUCCUCCUUAUGAUGUAUGCUAGGUUAUGGAAGAUGUAAAAUAUUCAACUUUUUCCUCCUUUUUUUGGACUUUGUAUUUUACUGCAUGUUUUCUUCAUUUUUAAUCAAUAAAGAGUAAAUUGUC